CACCACUCUAGAAUGGUUCGAUACCCCCAUCUACUGCUCCCUCAGAAAAAGCAAAAGAGAGGAGUCAGGCGUGGUGGCGCGCGCCUGUAAUCCCAAUUGCUCGGGAGGCUGAGGCGGGAUCAUCGCUGGAGCCCAGGAGUUCGAGGCCAGAGACCCCCUCUCAAAGAAAAAAAAAGCGAUGAAACGAGAACCCUCCAUAGUCUGAGCCUCAUUAAACCGUCCAGUUCUCCCAACCUGGACCCCUACCACGGCCUCCGCCUCUAUUCCGCAUUGACGCACACUCUCACAUUAACAGGCCAGGUUCCAUAGGCAGUUCUUACCAAGAAGAUGUCGAUUCCAUUCUCCAACACCCACUACCGAAUUCCACAAGGAUUUGGGAAUCUUCUUGAAGGGCUGACACGCGAGAUUCUGAGAGAGCAACCGGACAAUAUACCAGCUUUUGCAGCAGCCUAUUUUGAGAGCCUUCUAGAGAAAAGAGAGAAAACCAACUUUGAUCCAGCAGAAUGGGGGAGUAAGGUAGAAGACCGCUUCUAUAACAAUCAUGCAUUCGAGGAGCAAGAACCACCUGAGAAAAGUGAUCCUAAACAAGAAGAGUCUCAGAUAUCUGGGAAGGAGGAAGAGACAUCAGUCACCAUCUUAGACUCUUCUGAGGAAGAUAAGGAAAAAGAAGAGGUUGCUGCUGUCAAAAUCCAAGCUGCCUUCCGGGGACACAUAGCCAGAGAGGAGGCAAAGAAAAUGAAAACAAAUAGUCUUCAAAAUGAGGAAAAAGAGGAAAACAAGUGAGGACACUGGUUUUACCUCCAGGAAACAUGAAAAAUAAUCCAAAUCCAUCAACCUUCUUAUUAAUGUCAUUUCUUCCUGAGGAAGGAAGAUUUGAUGUUGUGAAAUAACAUUCGUUACUGUUGUGAAAAUCUGUCAUGAGCAUUUGUUUAAUAAGCAUACCAUUGAAACAUGCCACUUGAAGAUUUCUCUGAGAUCAUGAGUUUGUUUACACUUGUCUCAAGCCUAUCUAUAGAGACCCUUGGAUUUAGAAUUAUAGAACUAAAGUAUCUGAGAUUACAGAGAUCUCAGAGGUUAUGUGUUCUAACUAUUAUCAAAUGAAUAAAUCCUCUCUAUCACAUCCCCCAAAAAUGUUCUUUAGCUCCUGUUUCACUCCUAGUGGUAAAGAAUUUCACUGCUUUUUAAGGAUAGUCUAUUUAAUUUUGGAAUUUUUAGAAAGAUAAGCUGGGACAAAAAUCUGCCUCCUUCAGCCUGGCCAACAUGGUGAAACCCCAUGUCUACUAAAAGUACAAAAAUUGGCCAGGCGUGGUGCGCACACCUGUAAUCCCAGCUACUCGGGAGGCUGAGGCAGGAGAAUCGCUUGAACCUGGGAAGUGGAGGCUGCAGUAAGCCGAGAUCGCACCACUGCACUCCAGCCUGGGCGACAGAGCAAGACUCUGUCUCAAAAACAAAACAAAACAAAAAAAAGCCUCUGCCUCCUUGUAAGUUUAACCCACUGGUUUUCAUUUAUCAUACAUGUAUUCAAUCAUUUAUUGAAAAUGUAUUGAGUACUAUUCAUGUGCUGGGAAUUAGUAGUGAAUACUUGUUCUUACACUCAUACAACUUACAAUGCUUUAUUGUUUUGCUCUCCAGAACCACACAGAACAAGACUAAUAACAUCAUAUUGUAAAAAGCAAAAGCUAUCAUAUCAUGCUGCCUUCUUCAGUUAAAACUUCCCAAGUUUUUAAAUAUACAAUGGUAAUGCCUGUUUAACAAACUCAGAGGCUUUAUCUCUUUUAUGUUUUCAAUGAUUCAUUCAAAUCCCUAGUGCCUUAGUUUUAGAAAGUUCCGUCUCUCCUUUUUGAGGCCUCUCCACCCUUGAUUGUCCAAGAAACUGAGGGUUCAUGUCUUAGACCAAAGGGUGCAGUUCUCUUCCCAAUACAAAAGGUAGAAAGUGGAGUCUUACCAUUUAGUUAAUGCUGUUGCCUUCUACCAUAAUGUUGUAGCAUAGUCCAGCAGACUGAGGUGAUUCUCUGGCUGGUUCCAAUUCCUGCCUGCACCAUAGUGGAUGGCCCAUGAUUUAGUUCCAGGAUUACAUCUCUCUUGGUUUAUAGUCACAAAGCCAGUGUUCCCCCAAAGCUUAAAAACAAGCCAGGAUGGCUCAGUCCUGAGGAGAUUCUAAAACCAGGUCUAUGUUGUCACAACAAAUACUCUCCUACAAACACUUUGAUCCUUGUCCUAGGCUUAGACAUGCUCUUUCUGCAAAGCAGUUUUAUUUCAGGUGCCUCACUGCCCUUCCCUGGCACUGAGCCUUUAUCAGGCUCUGCAACAGAGGUUCCCCCAAGUGAUCGCCACUCAAACACAGUUGAUUCACACCAACCCUUUCAAGGUUGUGGCUUUCAUUCUCUAAUGUCCACUCAUACAGGCAGCCUUUCUCCUUCCAAAAUCUUGCUGCCACUGUAGAGAGUUUCAUGCUAGCUAAACACAAGUCUCUAAUAUCCCCCUUCCUCUCCUCCUUAACCCCUCUCCUCCAGGCUUACAGAGGAAAAGAAAUCAGUUCUCCUCCAGGAUUCCAGCUGUUCGUCCCUCCCAUUCCACUGAAAGCACCAGCUUCUAACACCUUCCCCUCUCAGACAGAGCCAUCCUGCUUAGCGGAUUGUCAAGGGGGGACCCAGAAUUUAUGCAAAGACUUAGAUUCCCUGACCUGGAGAGAUCAGAAGAGGAAAAAAGGGAUUUUUUCCCUAGUGAGUAUAUAGCAGGAAAAAAAAAAAAGAUGAGUUAGCUUUUUCAGUAAUUCUCCUGUUAUACACAUAAAGUGACUAGCACUAUGCAUUCCAUACACACACACACACACACACAGAUCUCAUGGUAGUGAUAUUGGUAGUGAAGGAGGAAAAGGAAAAGGUGAGCAAUGGAUGUGAUAUUAUGAGAACAACACAUAUGAAUGACACUUUAUUAGAACUUAUCUGGUUUUCCUCUUAUCUCUCUGGCUGUUCCUUCUCAAUUCCCUUCACUGGUAACUCUUCAACUCCCCAACCACUAAAUGCUAAGUGCCCUUAGGCUCAGUCUUUCGACCCCAUUUCUACACUCACUUGAUUUCCUGCAGUUUCAUAGCUUUAAAAUCCAAUCUUCUUAAUGAUCACUCCCAGACCUUUCUCUCCUCUGCCUGCGAACUUCUAUAUUCAACUGCCUACAUAACAUCCCCAUUUGGAUGUCUAUAGGCAUCUCAAAAGUAACAUAUAAAAAAUGAAUCCUGAUAUUGCCCCCAAAUCUGAAACUUCCCCCACACCCAAGUUUUUCCAUUCAAAAAUGGCUGCUCCAUUCUUCCAUUUGCUCAGGCCAAAAACCUUGGAUUCAUCUUUAAUGCGUCACUUUCUUUCACACCCCAUAUACAAUCUAUCAGCAAAACCUGUGGGCUGUACCUAUAAAAUAAUACUCAGAAUCUGCCUACUUCUAACCACUUCCAUUGUUACCGCCUUGGUCCUAGUUCCCAUGAUAGCCUUGUGAAUUAUUGCAAUAACCUAUAUUGGCCAGUGAUUAUCUCACUACUACUGCACAACCCAUUCCAAAGUUAGUGGUUUAAGACAAUUAUAUUUUCUCCUGGGUCUGUAGGUCAGUGGUAAUGUAGCUAAGCUAGGCUGGACUACAAUCUCAAGGUUAGGUUCAGGUCAGCUCUAAGCUGUGGGUUUGUGGGCUGACAGGAAGGUCUGCUUCAGGCUGUGGGCCCAAGGGUCAGCUGCAGCACAGUGCCUCUGCUUCACGUGUCCUUUUCUGAGCCCCUGCUGAAAGACGUUAUCCAGGACAAGCUCUUCUCAUGCUGGUCACAGAAGACAAGCAGGAAAACCCAGCAUGCAAGAAUAUUUCAAGCUUUUGCUC